GUUCUCCCCUCCCGCACUCCUGGAGAUAGACGCUCAAGCCUGACGCCUCUGAAAAGGCAGCAGCAGUCGCCUUAUCCAUAGACCUCAGGAAAUUCGCUUUGACCGAUGCAUGCUUCAGGCUCUGGCUCGAGCUGAGGGGAAUAACCGGGCAGAUGUCUGAGUCCUUAAAAAAGACAAGAUAAAACCAAAAUGCAUCACCAACACACAACCAAUUGAUGUGCUGGCAUCUUAGCUUGGCCCUGCAGAGGCAGAGAGAAAAGAAGAGGAGCUGUUGCGAUUUCCACAUCUAACAGCUUCUGGCUAUUUCGCAACUGCUGGGUUUGAGUCCUACUGUUGCCGUGGCUGAAAAGAGAAGUAAAAUCCAACUUGUGAGACCACGCACAAGGAAUUAGGCUUUGGCUGCAGCGGUGCUGAAGCCCAUGCUAUGACAGAAGAAGCAGGCCUUUGAAGCUAUCCUCGGGUUAAGAAAUGGUGCCCUAAAGAGGCAAGCAUCCCUUUCUCCGUUCUGCUGUAAGACACCACAUCUGAAGGAGACAGACUUGAGGCAUUCACAAGCAUCCAAGGAUACUGGCUCACUGCUGGCUUCCUGUACUUUCUUGAGAAAAGUGUUUUCUUUUUACUGACUCUCACUGCUUCCUUUUGGCCUGGUACCACUGGUGGAACCUGGCAGAUAAUGGGAUUUGAGGAGUUAAGUAUCUGUUGACACUGCAGAUACUCUUAAAUUAGUUAAUCAGACUCAAAUGGGUCAGUGCUUUCCCUUGAUCUUUUGUUGAAGCCUUUUCCAGAACGUUGUCUCCAAAGUGCAUCCUCCCUUUGGUCUGGAAGUUCUGUGGCUACCCUGUACCACUGGGGUCAACGUUUUCCAGUUGGAAGAGGACUACAGGGAGAGAGGGCGGGGUUAUUGGAAGAAGAAGAAGAAAAAAAGAACUAGAUAAAGGAGGGCACAUCCCUCUCACUCCCGCCUUUCCCCUUACCUUUCUGUCUCUCGGGACCCUUAUUUCUUCGUCACGGUGUCCAGGACCAUUUUGACCCUGUCGGCCCCGGCACCCCCCCGCCGCACCCCAGCCCCGAGCAUGGGGACGGCGCUGCUCCAGCGCGGGGGCUGUUUUCUUCUGUGCCUCUCGCUGCUGCUCCUGGGCUGCUGGGCGGAGCUGGGCAGCGGGCUGGAGUUUCCGGGCGCCGAGGGCCAAUGGACGCGCUUCCCCAAGUGGAACGCCUGCUGCGAGAGCGAGAUGAGCUUCCAGCUCAAGACUCGCAGCGCCCGCGGCCUCGUGCUCUACUUCGACGACGAGGGCUUCUGCGACUUCCUGGAGCUGAUUCUGACGCGCGGCGGCCGCCUGCAGCUCAGCUUCUCCAUCUUCUGCGCUGAGCCUGCGACGCUCCUGGCCGACACGCCGGUUAACGACGGCGCCUGGCACAGCGUGCGCAUCCGCCGCCAGUUCCGCAACACCACGCUCUUCAUCGACCAGGUGGAGGCCAAGUGGGUGGAGGUCAAGUCCAAGCGCAGGGACAUGACGGUGUUCAGCGGCCUUUUCGUCGGGGGGCUGCCCCCGGAACUGCGCGCCGCGGCGCUCAAGCUCACCCUGGCCUCGGUGAGGGAGCGGGAGCCCUUCAAGGGGUGGAUUCGUGACGUGAGGGUCAACUCCUCGCAGGUCCUGCCCGUGGACAGCGGCGAGGUGAAGCUGGACGAUGAGCCGCCCAACAGCGGCGGGGGAAGCCCGUGCGAGGCGGGCGAGGAGGGCGAGGGCGGGGUGUGCCUCAACGGAGGUGUGUGCUCCGUGGUGGACGACCAGGCCGUGUGCGACUGCUCGCGAACCGGCUUCCGCGGCAAGGACUGCAGCCAAGAAAUAAAAUUCGGUCUUCAGUGUGUUUUGCCGGUGCUGUUACAUGACAAUGACCAAGGAAAAUACUGUUGUAUAAAUACAGCAAAGCCUCUAACAGAAAAAGACAACAAUGUGGAAGGUCUGGCGCACCUGAUGAUGGGCGACCAAGGUAAAAGUAAAGGAAAAGAAGAAUAUAUUGCCACGUUCAAAGGAUCUGAAUACUUCUGCUACGACUUGUCUCAAAACCCCAUUCAAAGCAGCAGUGAUGAAAUAACUCUGUCAUUUAAAACCCUUCAGAGGAAUGGACUGAUGCUUCACACUGGGAAAUCGGCUGAUUAUGUCAAUCUUGCCCUGAAAAAUGGAGCUGUCUCUCUGGUCAUUAAUUUGGGAUCAGGGGCCUUUGAAGCACUAGUGGAGCCUGUGAAUGGAAAGUUUAAUGAUAAUGCCUGGCAUGAUGUGAAAGUCACCAGGAAUCUGCGUCAGCACUCAGGCAUUGGACACGCUAUGGUAAACAAACUACAUUGUUCGGUGACAAUAUCAGUGGAUGGGAUUCUUACCACAACGGGCUACACGCAAGAAGAUUAUACCAUGCUGGGGUCUGAUGACUUUUUCUAUGUUGGAGGCAGUCCCAGCACAGCCGACCUUCCAGGGUCACCAGUCAGUAACAACUUUAUGGGCUGUCUCAAAGAGGUUGUAUAUAAAAAUAAUGAUGUGAGGCUGGAAUUAUCUCGACUUGCCAAGCAAGGAGAUCCUAAGAUGAAGAUCCAUGGAGUGGUGGCAUUUAAAUGUGAGAAUGUUGCAACUUUAGACCCAAUCACCUUUGAAACCCCAGAGUCUUUCAUCUCUUUGCCUAAAUGGAAUGCAAAGAAAACUGGCUCCAUAUCAUUUGAUUUCCGUACAACAGAGCCAAAUGGCCUCAUCUUAUUUAGCCAUGGCAAGCCAAGACAUCAGAAAGAUGCCAAGCACCCACAGAUGAUAAAGGUGGACUUCUUUGCUAUUGAGAUGCUAGAUGGCCACCUCUACCUCCUCCUGGACAUGGGGUCAGGUACUAUAAAAAUAAAAGCCCUGUUGAAGAAAGUGAAUGAUGGAGAAUGGUAUCAUGUGGACUUCCAGAGAGACGGACGGUCAGGUACCAUUUCUGUCAACACGUUGCGUACUCCCUACACUGCUCCUGGUGAGAGUGAGAUUCUGGACCUGGAUGAUGAGUUGUACCUGGGGGGGCUGCCAGAAAAUAAAGCUGGCCUUGUCUUCCCCACCGAGGUGUGGACUGCUCUGCUCAACUAUGGCUACGUGGGCUGCAUCAGGGAUUUGUUCAUCGAUGGCCAAAGCAAAGAUAUCCGGCAAAUGGCUGAAGUUCAAAGUACUGCUGGAGUGAAGCCUUCCUGCUCAAAGGAAACAGCAAAACCGUGCCUUAGCAACCCUUGCAAAAACAAUGGCAUGUGCAGGGAUGGGUGGAACAGAUAUGUCUGUGAUUGUUCCGGAACAGGCUAUCUUGGCAGGUCCUGUGAGAGAGAGGCAACGGUUUUGAGCUAUGAUGGGAGCAUGUUUAUGAAAAUUCAGCUCCCCGUAGUCAUGCAUACGGAGGCUGAGGAUGUUUCCUUACGGUUCCGAUCCCAGCGUGCAUAUGGCAUUCUGAUGGCAACCACUUCUAGAGACUCUGCUGACACCCUCCGCCUGGAGCUAGACGCAGGACGUGUGAAACUGACGGUCAAUCUAGAUUGUAUCAGGAUUAACUGUAAUUCCAGCAAAGGUCCCGAGACUCUUUUUGCUGGCUAUAACCUCAAUGAUAACGAGUGGCACACAGUGCGUGUAGUUCGGCGUGGAAAAAGUUUAAAGUUAACAGUGGAUGACCAACAGGCCAUGACAGGUCAAAUGGCAGGUGAUCAUACUAGGCUGGAGUUCCAUAACAUAGAGACUGGCAUCAUCACAGAACGACGGUAUCUUUCUUCUGUCCCCUCCAACUUCAUUGGACACCUGCAGAGCUUGACAUUUAAUGGAAUGGCAUACAUUGACCUGUGUAAAAAUGGCGACAUAGAUUACUGUGAGCUUAAUGCCAGAUUUGGCUUCAGGAACAUCAUAGCAGAUCCUGUCACCUUCAAGACCAAAUCGAGCUAUGUUGCCUUAGCUACCUUGCAAGCCUACACUUCUAUGCAUCUUUUUUUCCAGUUCAAGACAACAUCCCUAGAUGGAUUAAUUCUAUAUAACAGUGGGGAUGGAAAUGACUUUAUUGUGGUUGAAUUAGUUAAAGGGUACUUACAUUACGUGUUUGAUUUGGGAAAUGGUGCUAACCUCAUCAAAGGAAGCUCAAAUAAACCUCUCAAUGACAAUCAGUGGCACAACGUGAUGAUAUCAAGGGACACCAGCAACCUCCACACUGUAAAGAUUGACACAAAAAUCACAACGCAAAUCACCGCCGGAGCCAGGAACUUAGACCUCAAGAGUGACUUAUAUAUAGGAGGAGUAGCUAAAGAAACAUACAAAUCCUUACCAAAACUUGUACAUGCCAAAGAAGGCUUUCAAGGCUGCCUGGCAUCAGUUGAUUUAAAUGGACGGCUUCCGGACCUCAUCUCCGAUGCUCUUUUCUGCAACGGACAGAUCGAGAGAGGAUGUGAAGGGCCCAGCACAACCUGCCAAGAGGACUCAUGUUCCAAUCAAGGUGUGUGCUUGCAACAAUGGGAUGGCUUCAGCUGUGACUGUAGUAUGACUUCCUUCAGUGGACCACUCUGCAAUGACCCUGGGACGACAUAUAUCUUUAGCAAAGGUGGUGGACAAAUCACGUAUAAGUGGCCUCCUAAUGACCGACCCAGUACACGAGCAGACAGACUGGCCAUAGGUUUUAGCACUGUUCAGAAAGAAGCCGUAUUGGUGCGAGUGGACAGUUCUUCAGGCUUGGGUGACUACCUAGAACUGCAUAUACACCAGGGAAAAAUUGGAGUUAAGUUUAAUGUUGGGACAGAUGACAUCGCCAUUGAAGAAUCCAAUGCAAUCAUUAAUGAUGGGAAAUACCAUGUAGUUCGUUUCACGAGGAGUGGUGGCAAUGCCACGUUGCAGGUGGACAGCUGGCCAGUGAUCGAGCGCUACCCUGCAGGAAACAAUGAUAACGAGCGCCUGGCGAUUGCUAGACAGCGAAUUCCAUAUCGACUUGGUCGAGUAGUUGAUGAAUGGCUACUCGACAAAGGGCGUCAGCUCACAAUCUUCAAUAGCCAAGCAACCAUAAUAAUUGGCGGGAAAGAGCAGGGCCAGCCCUUCCAGGGCCAGCUCUCUGGGCUGUACUACAAUGGCUUGAAAGUUCUGAAUAUGGCAGCCGAAAACGAUGCCAACAUCGCCAUAGUGGGAAAUGUGAGACUGGUUGGUGAAGUGCCUUCCUCUAUGACAACUGAGUCAACAGCCACUGCCAUGCAAUCAGAGAUGUCCACAUCAAUUAUGGAGACUACCACGACCCUGGCUACUAGCACAGCCAGAAGAGGAAAGCCCCCGACAAAAGAACCCAUUAGCCAGACCACAGAUGACAUCCUUGUGGCCUCAGCAGAGUGUCCCAGCGAUGAUGAGGACAUUGACCCCUGUGAGCCGAGCUCAGGUGGGUUAGCCAACCCAACCCGAGCAGGCGGCAGAGAGCCGUAUCCAGGCUCAGCAGAAGUGAUCCGGGAGUCCAGCAGCACCACGGGUAUGGUCGUUGGGAUAGUAGCCGCUGCCGCCCUGUGCAUCCUUAUCCUCCUCUAUGCCAUGUACAAGUACAGAAACCGGGAUGAAGGCUCAUACCAUGUGGACGAGAGUCGAAACUACAUCAGUAACUCAGCACAGUCCAAUGGGGCUGUUGUAAAGGAGAAACAACCCAGCAGUGCGAAAAGCUCCAACAAAAAUAAGAAAAACAAGGAUAAAGAGUAUUAUGUCUGAUCCCAAGAUCUUAAAUGGACACUUGUAUAGAAAUAGUCUUCAUUUUAUCUGAGACAUAAUAUAAACUUAUUUACUUUCCUUUUUAUGAAGCACAUACAAAAGAAGACAGGGAAUGCAAUCAGGAAGGAAAGACUUUUUAAAAAAUAAAAACAAGUAUCUCAUGCUCUUGUUUCUCAAAAAAGAAAAACAAAAAACAAAAAACAGGGGCCAAUAAAUUCCCUAACAUCCACAGUGUUUUCAUUUACUCUGCUUGUCUUUAUGUUGCUGGAACAUUUCUAAAAGACAGUGAUGACCGCACGCAUUCAUAAAGCAAAGGAGUACUACAGCAUCAAGGCACAACACAAAAACCAACACAAAACAUAACACAAAAAAGAAGCUACCUAUGAUCCUGGAUUUAGCCAAAGUGCUAGCGCUUUCCUGAGAAGUCAGUCCAAUUGCCAGAGAAGACUGUCCUUUUGAGUGACUCAACCUGCAAACCUUUAAGAGUUUGCCGCCUGGUGCAACUGGAGCAGUGGUUGGAACUUGCAUUUGAAACAAAGUGCUGGCUUUUUUGAAGACUUGUGUAGGAACACAUUCAAAAAGCCCCUUUCUGGUUGUGAGAGAGGAAAAAAAAGUAUGGAGGCCUUAUUUUCAAAAAUGUGAAAUAUAAGGCACGUUUUCACACAAAAUUUCAAAACAAAAACAAGAGGGCAUAGAUGCAAUCAUUGGGAAAUUUUCAUGCACGCUUAUUAUGUUAUUACAUAUGUUUAUAUAAAAUCCAUCUCUGUGUGCUUUCUGGACUGUGAUAAGUGACGUUUUAUAGCCUGUUGUAUAGAAAAUGCAAAAUAUAUCUCUGCUCUUCAGCCAUUUUUGGUAAAUUCAAUGUUAUAAGUGUUGCUAAGUAUAGGGAGUUUUAUGACAUCAGAGCAACAAUUAUUUCAGUUGGGUUUUUCUUUUUUUUUGCCACCAUUAUAAAUUGCCACAAUUACUUUUAUUUUUUAAAGAAAUUACAGUGUAGUGUUUAUUCUAAGGAAGAUAUGUAUGAAUGUAUAUACAAAGACUCAGCUACUUCUUUUCUUAUAUGUACAGCCUUCAUUCUGUUGCAAUUAAGUUUUAGUACUUGUAUGAAAGGUGUGAAUUAGAAAGUCACAUAUAUACAUAUGUAUCUUAUAAUCUUUUCUCCCUGAAAUACUCACAUUCCCACAUACAUUCACUAUUUUCACACACACACACACACACACACACACACACACACACACACACACACGAAUCCACAGCAAUCCAUCAGAUAUGCUGGAAGAUCCAAACGUGCAUACAGUAGCAAAUAUUUAUUGACAAAUUGAAAAGCAGGAAGGAAGAGGGUUGUGCCAAGGUAUUGAUGACAAAUGGGGUGAUUUGCUUCAUUGAGAUCUUGCUCCCAGGUAACCUUAAGAAGAUUUUAGUCCCUAAAGAAAUGAACCUUUCCUUAUCAAAUAGAAUAUCACUGAUAUACUGCUGCAUGAAUAAGAACCAUUAUGUGGGCAGGUUAUGGAAGCAAAAUUGGUUAAUCUACACCUUAACUCUGGCUGCUGCAAUUGAAAACUUUCUUUCUAAUAAAAUAAUAUAUAUAUCUCUGAAUCUGAUGUGCAUGAUGAACAUUUCUGGAAAGUAAACACUUUCUCUCGACUAAGAAAGUAUUUUUCAGUAAUUUUUGAUUCUGUAUUACUACCCACUUAAAAAAUCAUUCUCUGUUAAUUAUUGACUAUGUUUUAACUUUUCUGGUUUUACAUAUAUAUCAUUAAAUAUAGUUUUAGUUUAACACAUUAAGUAGUGGAAAAGUAUAGAUUAUACACUUGUUUUGCAUAUUAUUCAAUGAUGUUCACAGCAAUAAAUUACUAAUAUGAGAAGGUAGUGCAAAAAAUGCAUUAUUACAUUGCAAGUUGAUGUUUCAGGAAAAAUUGGUUGCAUUACUUGAAUACCUUCUAAAAGAACGAUAAAAAAUUUUGUAGAAGAGAAGAAUAUCUUUCCAAUUAGCUUUAAUCAGCAAAGGCAAAAAAUGCAAAACAUCUUUUGUGAUACUUUAGUUGAUGAAAAAAAAGCCAAGAAGUGGCCUGGAUUUCAGACAUACAGCACCUUAGAAAUAUGUAUAAUUCAUAGCAAAUCACCACUAUCUAUGGUUGCCAAGUAAUUGUUGUGUACAAAGAAAUUUAGUGGCUUUUUAUGACCCAGAAAGUAGAAGGUAUAAAAUGAAAAUUUAAUAUCCAUUGCUUCUUUUCUAGAUUUUCAUUUUUUUUAAUUUGCCACAUUAAAUAAUUCACGAGUCUUUUCUUUUCCCCCGUCUCAUUCAGUCUUACUCAGGGAAAGCCAGUUAAAUAAGAAGGGAAGUGUAAAACUACUAAUUUACAGCUUGAAGGGUUUUUUUUUUUAAGAUUGCUUUUCUAUUUUAUCUAUUAAGCUUGAACCAGUUUCCAUCUGGAAAGAUUCUAAAAUAUAAUAGAAAAUAAAUUGAAUAAUGGUAAUUUUAAGCAGUAUAUCUAUGAAAUGUGUUGUUUGGGAUUGAUUUCAAUGUUUCUCCCCAGCGUAAAUUUUAAAGUUACAUGCAAUGAUUGAUAUAGUUUAUUAUCAGCAAAAUUAUUUCUAAUAUUAUUGGCUUACACAAACUCUAGCAAAAAUUAUUUUUUCCUCAAUGGAAAAAGAAAAGAGAGGAACAGAGUUAGAAAGAGAAAAUGACUUGAAUCCCAAGUAUCUUCAUACCAAACAUAUCAGGGUUCCCUGCAUAGUUUGCAGUUGAUUGAGGAUUUCACACGACUUGGCAUAAAUUUGAUUACAUCUCUAGACUGUAACUUUUCUGAUUGAUUAUGCUUCUUUUUUAUCCAUGUAAUGUGUUGCCUUUUUUAAAAGAACAAAUACUACAAUAACGUGUGAAGUGGUCAAUCCCUAAGACAUCAAAGAAAGGCCACAUAACCCUACCCUUCUAGUGCUUUGUGUGAUUGGGUAUCAAAGGGGUUUUCUUCUUCUUUUUUUGUUUGUUUGUUUUUCUGUUGCAAGGCCAAUUUAUCCAUUAUUGGAAAUGCUAAGCAAGUGGAAUUUACUGUUUUGUUAAUAAAAUAUUUCUUAAUACAACUGUGAUUUAUUGAUUUUAAAAAUUAUAUGCGGCACCAUUUCGUGCUUAAGUGGGAAAGUAAAGAAGGCUGCAUUUGAAGGGAAGACCCAUCCUUAUAUUAUAGAGGAAGAAUGUUGACUCUCUUUUUUCUGGAUUUAACUAGUCAUUAAAGACCUCUAUAUUCAUACACUUAAAGAUGUAGCCAUUAAAUGUACUUUUGUUAUAUUUGUUCAUCUUGAUAUGCCAGAAACCAUAAACUCAUACAGUAUUAGUUGCAAACAAUAUUAAAAUACUAAUUUCAUAAAUAUGCUUUUUCUCUAUAAAAGACAAUGGAAUCCAAGUUAAGUAAACCUGUGAUUAAAUUCCAACACUAUCACAUA